AGUUUCAGCACAGUGCCAUUAUGAUGGAUGUUUACAUCUCUUCAUUGAGAGCCAAUUAUCUCGCUUUUGUGUGAGGCCCAAGGAUCACUCAUGCUUCCAGGCUGCACAGAGCACUGUUGGAUCUAGCUGAACGAAUUGUUUUCUCUGUCUCUGGGUAUCAACGGUUUCUGUACAGCACAGAUUAUGACAGCGUCUUUCUUAAGAUUCUGUGGACCUGACUGACACUAGAAAAGCCGCAGUAGCAUGUGACAUGGAAGUUUAUAUUAUCAGGGUGUGCUCACCUGGUUGCAAAUUUGAGACCAAAGUUUUACUUUAACACUUGGAGCUGGUAAAGGAUGUUUUAUUCAUUGUGUUUCUGACAGAUGGAACAAGUUAAGGUUACCUUCUCAAUAUGAGGACUAAAGCUUUUAGCCAAUAUUUGUGGAGAAGACACAUUUAAGAUUUUCUUUUGCCCAUACAUGCAAUGUUAUGGAGGCUGUGACCACAUUUUAGGCAAGAAACUGAAAGAACAUCAAGCACCUAUCUGGAUGUCUCCAAAGCCUCAUCUGGAUAAAAUAUCCAAUCUAUUUUUCAAUCAGCCUUUUUUUUUCCUUUUUCAACCUCAGACAAUUGCUUUUGGGGUCCUAGAGUCCCUUGAAAGUUAUGAUGGAAAUAGGAGACCUAAAGUUCAGGUGACUGAAGGGCUGAAGCAGGAAGGAAAAACGUCUGGGAGGACAGGUAGACAGAGGAAAGAGGUCUGAAGAGGCACAUAUCAAAAGAUUCAAGAAAGCUGAAGGGAAGAUUGAAGGUAGUAAAAGGAUGAAGGAGGAGCAGAAGCAAUGGGAAGGAAGAGAUCUCAGAGGACUCACUUCGGGAAAAUCUUCAGUUUCCCAAAGAGAUCCUGAAGUCUCAAAUUAUCCUUAACAAAACCAUGACCACAAGAAAGGAAGUGGAGUAUACGAUCAGUGAGAGUUUAAGAAGGGGGUUUCCGUUGACUAAAAAGUUACCGUGGGAGAAAUAGGAUCAAAUAGAACAGAGUUGCCUCACAAAGAACCAAGGAAAAUAUUUCAGCUCAGGGAUUCAAGAAGUAAAUUCCCACUCAAAGACAGAAACAGGAAGUAAGAUUUACAAUUCAGCCAGUACCUUCCUAACAGAGAAGCAUGUGACUAUACCAACUUCUUACAAAAAGAAACAGGACUAACUCAGCCUCUGUAUAGUGUACUCAGGCUCUCUCAGCCCUCACUGUGCUUCAACAGACUUAUCAUUUGGAGCACUGGCUCAGGAGUCGAAAUCACCAAUGGCUCAUCCAUCAAUCAACCAGAAGUGAAGACGAAAGCUUCAAAGAAGAGAAUGUUUAAAUUUCAUCAAAUGAAACAUAUUUUUGAAAUACUUGAUAAAAUGAGAUGCCUGAGAAAACGUUCUACAGUGUCAUUCUUGGGAGUUCUUGUCAUUUUUCUCCUUUUUAUGAACUUGUACAUUGAAGAUAGCUAUGUUCUGGAAGGAGACAAACAACUUAUAAGGGAAACAUCCACACAUCAACUGAAUUCAGAACGCUAUGUUCAUACUUUCAAGGAUUUAUCUAAUUUCUCAGGAGCCAUAAAUGUCACCUAUCGCUACCUAGCUGCCACACCUUUACAAAGAAAGCGGUAUCUUACAAUUGGACUUUCUUCAGUAAAGCGAAAAAAAGGAAACUAUUUACUUGAGACAAUUAAGUCAAUUUUUGAGCAAUCCAGCUAUGAAGAGCUGAAGGAAAUUUCAGUGGUGGUUCACCUAGCAGACUUUAAUUCUUCCUGGCGUGAUGCCAUGGUCCAGGAUAUUACACAGAAAUUUGCGCACCAUAUUAUUGCAGGAAGAUUAAUGGUUAUACAUGCUCCAGAGGAGUAUUACCCAAUCCUAGAUGGCCUUAAAAGAAAUUACAAUGAUCCAGAAGAUAGAGUCAAAUUUCGUUCCAAGCAAAAUGUAGAUUAUGCUUUUCUGCUUAAUUUUUGUGCCAAUACUUCAGACUAUUAUGUAAUGCUUGAAGAUGAUGUUCGAUGUUCAAAAAAUUUCUUAACUGCCAUCAAGAAAGUCAUUGCAUCCCUAGAAGGAACUUACUGGGUAACUCUUGAAUUCUCUAAGCUUGGCUACAUUGGUAAACUCUAUCAUUCUCAUGAUCUCCCACGUUUGGCCCAUUUUUUAUUAAUGUUUUAUCAAGAAAUGCCUUGUGAUUGGCUAUUGACUCAUUUCCGUGGUCUGUUGGCUCAGAAAAAUGUGAUCCGUUUUAAACCAUCUCUCUUUCAGCACAUGGGCUAUUAUUCAUCAUACAAAGGGACGGAGAAUAAGCUGAAGGAUGAUGAUUUUGAAGAGGAGUCAUUUGACAUUCCUGAUAACCCCCCUGCAAGUCUGUACACCAACAUGAAUGUGUUUGAAAAUUAUGAAGCAAGCAAGGCUUACAGUAGUGUUGAUGAGUACUUUUGGGGGAAACCACCUUCAACAGGAGAUGUUUUUGUGAUUGUAUUUGAAAAUCCAAUUAUAAUAAAAAAAAUUAAAGUAAAUACUGGAACAGAAGAUCGGCAAAAUGAUAUUUUGCAUCAUGGAGCCCUAGAUGUUGGGGAAAACGUUAUGCCUAGCAAACAAAGGAGACAAUGUUCUACUUACUUAAGACUAGGAGAAUUCAAAAAUGGAAACUUUGAAAUGUCAGGUGUAAAUCAAAAAAUUCCAUUUGAUAUACAUUGUAUGAGGAUAUAUGUCACCAAAACACAAAAGGAAUGGCUAAUUAUUAGGAGUAUUAGCAUUUGGACUUCUUAGCCAAUUAAAUCAGUAUGUUCAGUUUCUGAAGCAGUUCUUCCUGCUUCGUCUUUUGCUACCUUUGUCUUUUGGAGGGAAAGCAAUGGAUGGGAUAUGUUAAAAGAAACAUUAAUUACAUUGGCAGUUUUCAUUUAUACAUUGUUGACAUAAUUUUACUCUUAAUACACACUUGUAUUUAUUUUAACGUCUGAAGUUGAAUAUCAGUCUAUAGCUAAUGCUACUUUCAUUUAUAUUUUUAAAUGUUCUUAGUUUUAAAAUUUCAACUGAUUGUCGAAAGGGUAAUAUGAAAGAUUUUAAAUGAAAAAAAUUUGUUGGAUGAUGAUUUUUGAAAAAUAGUCACCAACUGUAUAUACUUCCUCAAGAACUGAUAAUUCAUUAUAUCAUCAGAUAGCUUUUAUUAAGCAUCUGUGGGAAUAUACAGUUGGGUGGAAUGAUAAUCUGGUUUAUUUUUUCUGUAAACUUAAGUUUCCGUUGACUUCUGUACAUCUACAAUGAAUACCUCCUCAUAGAAGUGGUGUCUUUACAUAAUUUUUUGUGUAGGUGACACUAUGGAAAAAGAAAAAAAAGACUUAAAAAUAUCUCUCCCCUGAUUAUUUAUAUGAAAGGGGAUAUUGUUCAUUGUUUAAAAACAUUUAAUUGAGCACCUAUUGUUGAUAAAUUUUCUGGGGGAAGCAGUCUUUUUCAAGUUUCCCUUUUGAAAAAAAAAAAGAAGAGUUAAGCUCAAUAUUUUCAGGUUACAUUGAGUACCCACAUUUAAUAGAAUAAAUUAGGGAAGGCCUAUAGUAGUUAGCUCAUUCGUACAGACAUUUUCAGUAUAUGCAGAAAAUUUUUGGAAAUUGAUUUUAUACAUUUUGUAUUAAAAUCCAUGUGAUUGAAAUUAUUGUGAUUUAUCAUAUACCUUUUUGGAAUUUAAAUGGGUAUAUUAUAAAGGAGAAAAGUAAGAACCAUAGAAAUUAGUUGACUUUUCUAGAAUCAAAGAUCUAUUUCCUAGCAAGGCCAGAAUGAGAGAUCUGAUAUUCUGAUAACCAGACAAUGCUCUUUUUCUCGUAUGAUUUCUCCUGACAGAUUUAUGCUUUGUGUUCUAUUUGCUACAUGCCUGUCAGAUAAUAAGUUAUACCAUCUGGAAAUAGGUGGUACAAUUCCUGCAUAAAUAAUAUUAUCCUAAAUAAUGUCCUAAAUGAUGCUUUUUUGGUAUAAGCACCCAAAUAGUAAGCAAACUUGACUAAACUUUUCCUAAUAGGGAUUGGAGAGUGUGUCUUUACAAUGUGUCCGUUAAAGUAAUUCAGGACACCUUAGUGUGUCCUAAAGACAUUGGUUUUCAGAAUGUCCUGAGCUUGUCUCUUCCUUUUUGUUUUUUAAUGAACAGCAAAAACUAAGGGAUUUAUUAUAAAGGGAAAUGGAAGGUGCUUCAUAUAUGUUUAAGAAACUCAAGUACGUGUUCAUAUAGAUGACUCUGUGUGUGUGUGUGUGUGUGUGUGUGUGUGUGUGUGUGUGUGUGUGUGUGUGUGAAGGCUAGACUUUUGCUGGUAAGACAGAAUGAGGAAAUCUUCCUGCUCUUCCUUUUCAUACUGAAACACAAUCCUUAAGAUUUACUGGUAUGCUGUGGUGCAAACAACACUAGGAUAUUUUUAUUUUAUUCGUUCUCUGCAAAUAAAUGAGAAACUCAGAUAAAAAAUGGAAACUUUUUAUUUCAUUUAUAAACAGCUGUUGUGUAUUUUCUUUGUAUUCAGCUACUAAAGUGUUAGAAGAAAAACGAACCUUUCAUAAGAGGCUAAAUAUUAAUAUUUUGUGAGGCACCUAAAUCUUACAGUCAUAGGAAAAUAUGAACACUGCCACUAAAUUAUUAUCUUUACCUUGAUUUAGAGGAUACUUGCCAGACACCUAAAAAUGUUCUAUUUUCUUUAUUUUUCUUAUCUUUUAUUAACCGGCUAGUUGAUAGUAUUGUGUGUAUAUCUCAGAAGUUACAAAUGGCAUUAUUUUCUUCACUGUCAAUGAUAAAAGGUACACAAUUGUAUGCCAAAGACAUGUAAUAUCAAGAGCUAGGCAGACUCCCUGAAAUGAGUUGUAACCCCUUACAUAUUCUUCUGGGAAUGGCUUUCUAAAGAUCAGCUAUUGGUGUCUAUCAAUGUCUUAAAAAUGUUUCAAGAAACAUUGCUGAGGGUAGCAGUGAAGUUGGAUGUUUGCUAGGAAAUUAUGAAAACAAAUGUGACUCAGAGAGGUCAUUUCACAUUUUAUCUUUAUAUCCUCUCUUUACUAAACCUGUGUUUGGAUAAGUUGGUCAAUCAUCCAAGGAUCCUCUAUGUUUUCUUUACAGUUGACACUGGGUCAAUUUUCUAAGGAAAACACCUUGACAAAUAAAGCAUCUUCAUUAGAGGUCAGGAGGAAAAAUAACUAUUCUCUUUCAAAAGAAAAUCUGAACAAUUUUUUUAGCAUGGCCCAAUGUUCUAUUUCCUAUAUUUAGAAACUUUGAAUAAGGGUCUAGUAAUCUUGUCUCAGAGGCAUAGAAACAAAAGUACAGUUAUUAGGUUUAACUAUACUCAAACUAUUUGCUAUUUUUAAACAUUUUUGCUGUAAGUUUAUAUAUAUAUACAUAUAUAAUACAUAUAUACAUAUAUAUAAUAUAUAUAUACAUAUAUAUAUAAUUUUCUUUGUUAAAAAUAACAAUUGAAAAAGACUGGCAUGAGACAUGAAUGGCUGAGUCAUUUAAUUGCCAUACAAAUAAAAUGCUGACAGGUUUCAAGCAAAAAAUACAGUAUGCACCUUAAAUAAUGCCUCAGAAUUGUAUAAUUUAAGCUCACUAAAAACCUUACUUAGUCUUAAAAUUCUCCUUAGGGGAGCCUUUUCAGCAGUUAUGGACAUCAAAGAAAAAAGUAUCUUGUAAAAGCACAAUGAAAUUUAGAAAAUACACAUUUUAGUGGCAAUCACAAAUGUCAAUAUAAAAGAUACAUAAAAUAUGUUAAUGCAAGAACUUUUUCAUAUUCAUUGAAAACUAUAACUUUGUGCUAUUUAUAAAGUAGAUAUUUUCCAGGUAUGAAAAUAUAAUUUGGAAACCAACCUGUCGUUUAGAUCUAUUUCUUUCAUAUAGCUACACUAUGAGUUGUGAACAUUCCAUUUCUUACUGGGCCAGUAUUCUCUGGGAAUUUUUAUAAUGCUAUCAUAGAAAAACUGUUCUGUAUAAUAAUUAUAUAAAAAAUGAAACAAACAUUUUCAAAUUGUAAUAUAUGAUGUGGUAUGGAAAGUACCUACAUUUUUAGAUGCUCAAAUAUUGGCAUAUUUCAUGUCAGUAUUUGCCAAUUUGUCAACAAGUUUAUGGCAAAGAACAUGAUACCAGGAUUAACAUUGAAAACACUACAUCCAGUGCCAUCUAACAAUUGAAGGAAACAGUGUGUAAUUCUCUUCUUUUUCCUUGACAAUACAUCCAUCAACACAGUAAUGGCAUCAUAUUACUGAGUAAUAGAGCUCACACUUAAACUUUAUAAUAUUUAUUAUGGGAUCUACUGAUAAAAUGAUUUACCGUUUUGUACAAAUUCAACUGAUUUUGGGGGGUUUCUUGUAAGAUUUAAUAUUAAUUUUAGGAUAAUUUUAUCCUGUUUCUUUUGAUUCAUGAUCCCAAACUUUCUAGAUCUUGCUUCUGUCAUUCCACGUCUUAUUAUGCCUCCUCAGCUUUGUGUUUCAACAAAUUUUAUAUGCAUGCCUUUUGUCUUCAUGGGAGACAAAACAGAAGGUUCAUACAGACUUGAUUUUGACACCCAGUUCUGCAUUACCAGCCUCCCAAUAUGAGGAAAUUUACUUAACCUUCUUGAAACUCAGUUUCUACAUCUGUGAAUAGGAAUAAUUUUACCUCAUAUGUUUUUAAAGGUAGCAAUUUUACCUUGUAGCUCCUUGUAGAGCUGGAAUUGAGAUAACAUAAACUAGGCACACAAUAAAUAUUUGUUUCCUUUUUAUCCAUGUCACGUAUAUGUAACAGGAUAUGACCCUGGAAAACAUUACCAGAGGCCUUCAUUGUAAUCAAUAACAAUUAUAAAAUUUACUGCCCUUUAAAAAUGUUAUUCAGCCUACCUUUUCAUAUUUUGUCCAGAGAAUAUCAUGUGGAAUUAUACAGACACUUUCCUAAAAUCAAUAUAUAUUCCUGUCAUUCUAAUUUAUUACUCUAGAAACCUUAUCAAAAAUAUCAAAAUUGCCCCUAGUGCUCUCAUCACAAAUAAUAAUAUUCAUUUCUGUUUUAAGAAAUCUUGAUCCAUUUACAUUGAAAAACAAAGAAACAUAAAGUCAUUUCCUAGUUUCUAAGAUGUUGUUUAGAAUCUACCUUAAGCUCAGAAAUGCAGUCUUCAGAAUCUUUUUACUUUUUUUUUUUAAUGUCAGGAUCCGGUUCUCUGGCAUCUUUUCUAUCAUUGGCAAAAGUUAUCAAUGCACUGACCUAUAAAUUACCUUGGCACUGAUGUUUGAAAUAGGUAUCUUAUCUGCUAGUCUACUUUGAGUUUCAUUGUUGAGUUUUCCAUUACUUUGAAUUUCUUUGUUCAGAUUGGGGUUAUUCUUUUUAGGAAGAAAAAGGCCAUAACAAAAUUCAAUGUGAUUAGUUAUUGCCAUUUAUUUUUUGUUUGCUUUUAAACUUUUUUUUUAUUUAUCCCAAACAGAGGAUAUAUCUUUUAUUACUUUUUGGCAUGCUUUGAAAUGAUUUCAUUAUUGCAUAUGUGCAUGUGUGUAUCUACAUAUGGUUAAUCUCUCAAUCUGUGUGUAUGUAUAUAUACAUAUGUGUAUGUACAUAUGUGUAUAUAUGUAUACAUACUUGAAUAUUAUGUGAAUAUGUGUGUAUAUUUGUGUAUAUAUAUACAUAUAUACAUGUAUGUAUUUGUAUAUGUGUUGUGUAAGUGUGUCUGUGUGUAUGAGAGAAAGACAGAAGGAUAUGCACCAUUUGCAUUAUUUUUUAGCCUUUACACCUCCACUUAUUCUUGGAUUUUCCUGACACACUGUCCUCCUGGUUGUGUUCCUCUUCUGAACUUGCUUUUGCUUUCAUGUUCUCACUCAAAUCUUUUAUACAUGACAUCCUUUGAAAAUCACAGCACAUUAGAGAUCUUUGUGCAUCCUUUUAGAUACUUUAAAUUUAUUAAAAGUGUACUAGAGGAGGCCAUCUCUCUCAAAACAGAAUUUUUCUUUUAGAGUUUCAGGUUUAUGGUUUUUAUUUGAAUUCUUUAACAUUAAAAGAUCAAAAUAUGAGUUGCAUAGCAUUCUCUUUCUAAGCUAUAAAAAUAUUAAGAUAACAAGGUUGCACUUUCCCAAAGUUCUAGUCCCUUCCACCUCAUUAAUCUGUUCAUCACAUUUACUCCAAGUCCAGGGUAGAAUUUGCUUCAAUAAUCCCAAUAUUUUCUGAGAUGUUUAAUAUCCUAUUUUUAACAUUGAAAUUGAAAUGUAUGUUUGAGACCAUUUGCCAGAUAACUGGAUCUGAAUAUCUUUUCUGAAAAACAUGGAUUUGAGACCAAAGCAGUUUUUGAUUUGACUGUUGUUUCAGCUUUCAUUUCACUCUGUCUAGACGGUCUCUUAGAAGAUUUACCAAAAAGUUAAAUUGAUUAUGUGAGAAAGUGAUAGGUAAAUUGUAUAUGACCAUAGAAGUACAAUUAAAUUAAGAAUAUAGCAUGAUCAAAUUUUCACAUUAUAUUGGAUUAAAAAGUACCCUAAGUAGCCAUCUCCUUAAAGUAGGUGAGCCAAAGACAUAAUAAUAAAAUAUUCAAUAUUUUUCUAUAAAAUACAAAUUUCCAUGAGGCACACAUACAUUAAAUUUAAUAUAAAGAGAAUCAUUACUUUAUUUAAGAGUUGUUUAAAGGUGCACAACAACAGUGAGUUACCAAUAUUCAGAACCUUAGUCUAUAAUUUCAAUGUACUGUAAGUUACUACAGCUUUAACCACAAUAGCUGGCAUAACCUAAAUCAUUCUGCCCAAAUACAGGUAAUUAUAGUUUUGAUGUAUAAAAAUUACCAAAAUAAAUGCAUAUAUAAAGCAAUAGAGGCUGAGAGUGUUCAUAAUUGAAAGCUAACUAUUGCAAAAAUAUUUUAAAUAUUUAAUUUAUAGUGCACUCGAAGUUCUGGAAGAGACGUAGGAUUUGUCUCUUCCACCCUUUCCCUCACUUUACCGUUUAUUAUGAAGGUACCAAAAGUAUGGCACAGAGAUAUGUGGCAGUUCCACAUAUCUCAAUCAACAAAGCUCUAACUCUAUUAGAAACUAGACAUUUAAAAAGUACUUUUUUUGUAACUUCAUCUGAGUCAGGUUUCUCAUUGAAUAAUAAUCUGUCAGUUUUGUCUAUAGUAUGUUCCAAUUGGAAAAUGUUUAAGGUAGUACAUGCCUCUUUUCUCCAUAAAAUACCCCACAUUUGUUUAACUAUUUGACAUAGUCCUAUUUUUUCCAUCUUUAAUAAUUGAUAAAAUUUUCCCUACUUUUAAACAUAUGUAUGUAUUUUCUGCCACACUUAAACUUUGUUAUUCCACGUUGUAACUUACUUCAUCAAUGAGUGAAAGUAUAGUUCCAAAAAGUUAGAAUAAUUAUCUCAGAUCCUUUAUCAUAAUUGUCCAAUUAUCUCAGAUCCUUUAUCAUAAUUGUCCAUCCUUUAAUGUAAUCCGGUUUUCAAUACAAGUAACACUUGCAUUCUUACAACUGUGCAUUUUUGGUCACUAAAGGACCAUGUGACGAUAUCAGUAGUUGUCAGGAGUUAUUCACUACCCUUAGAAAAUAAACUCGGUAAUGUAAACUAUAUCCCACACUUUAACAAUUAAUACUGUUGAAUGACAUUGAAGGAUUGUAUCUUUUUUUAAUAAAGAAGCAAUAUAUUAAAAAUAAUUAAAACUCCUAAAGUCUUUUUUUUUGUUUUAGAAAUCAGUCUCAAUUUUCAAAAGGGCAUUUGAUAUCUGCUAAUAAAAUGAACAAAUAGUUUUUCUUUAAAUGAAAAUAUCUAUAAGCUUAGCUGUGUGUAGAAGUACAUAAUAAAUAAGUUGUCCAUUUUGAAUAAAAAUUAAAAUCCUAUUAAUGCAGUUGUAACUUCUCUUCUUAACAUUUCUUAAGCUCUAAAACAAACAUAAUUAGACACAUUUUCUGUUGCAUGUGGCAUCUUUACCCACCAUAAUUUGGUAAUCAGUCAUAUCAAAAUCACUUACAAGAACCAACUAUUUUUGGAAAAACAUUUAGAAAAUUUGUCACAAAUUGUCAAGAAGAUUUUCAAGACAUAUAUAUGAAUUGUCUGUAAUGUAAUGGUUGGGGAUAUUUUCAUUAAAUCCAUAAACCAAUGUAUGUAUGCUGCCCUCUAACUUUCUGCUGAGUUACUGUAGUCAAUGGUAAAUAUAGUCAAAGUAGAAAAGACACAUUCACCCUGAAUAUUCCCAACAACCUAUCUCUCAUUCAAUUCUGACUAUUGACAAAGUACUCCUUUCAAUUAUUGUGGUAAGGAGGCCUUUCUGAGCAUCCAGAUGUGUAAAAAUAACAACAGGGGAAAUGUUACAAACAUGAGGUAAAAGGAUGCAGAGGAAAAGUUGUACUUCAUGAUUUUGCCUCAAGCAAGUUCUUCUUUCCUGUCAGCAUUGCAAAUUACCAUAGCUCGACUUGCUUGUAUUCAAGCAAAUCAAAACUUGACUCCCUGAGAGGGUCAAAAGACAAUUUUGGUACGUAUCUAGUGUUUUUACUUACUAGAACAAACAGGUCAAGUUUAUUCUUAAUGAAGUUAAAAUUUCAAAUUAAACCUGAAGCUCUAGUGUUUUCCAUUUUACUAAGUGGAUAAACACUUUUCUGCCAUGGGAUGAACUACAAUGAGAUGUUUGAAUUGAUUUGGGCAAUUGAUUUGGGCAAUGAUGAGUCAUGUGUUUGCUACAAAAGUGAUACAAAAUAUAAGUGUCCUUCAAGUUAAAGCAAUCUAAACCGAUCAUCUUUGAAAAGUUAACAACAUAUUUUGUAAUAUUUGUUUCCUAGCAAAUUUUUCAGUUGUCCAAACCAAGGUAAUGUAGAUAAAGCUACAUAUUUUCACUCAGCGUACCACCAAAUAACUGGGUGCCCAAUAGUGUUGAUCUGAUGCACUACUAAAAUUAGUUACCAUAAAAAUUAUUUUCUUUUAUAAGAAGAAAGUGAAAUUUGUUUAAUUAUUUUGAUAUCUUUUAUCCUUAUGAAUAUAUAUAUCAAUGUUAAUUUUUUAUGAAUAAUUAAAUUUAUUAUAAAUGCACUAAUUUUUCAACAUUCUUCUGAUUUUCAUCAGUAAAUUGAAUAACCAUUGUUGCAAUGAAAUUUACAUAUUGCUCUCAUAAUAUGAAAUUUUACAAGGUAUAAUUUCACUUAACACAAACAAUAGUCCUCAUACCACUUUUUCAUUUUAACUUUAAUCUCAUUAUUUAUGUGAUUAAGUUUGCAAUUUUAGCCACUCAUGUGUUAGGAGCAAUAGAGAUUGACAUUAUGUAGGUAGGAAAAUACAUUUUUAGUAACUUAAGAAACAAGUUGUACAUACUAUAUCAACAUUUCACAUUAGUGAAUUUAUUAUCUUGCUGUAUAAACUUUAAUAAAAACAAUUAUUUUUAUUUAAAUUAUUUAAGGUUCCUCUAUUUGACUUCAAAGCAAAAUAAUAUCUGAAUUGUACAAGCACUGUGAAUUUGUAAUAGUCUAAUCACAGUCUAAUCACUAAAUUCAAUUAGUACUUUACUAAAUUUCUUACAGUAUGCUCAGGACAAAUAAUUUAUUGAAAUGAGUAUACUCAGGAUGGAGUUAUUUUCAUGCAAACUUAAAAAUUACAAGACAUGUUUAGAAGAAUUAUAGCUGGAUAACACUAAACAUUCACAAGUUUUAAGUUAGCAUAAGGGGAUUUAUAAGUAAUGUGCCUACGUUCAUAAUCAAUUUAACAGUUUUCACUAACUUGACCCAAUAAUUUAGGGUGUAUUUCCAGACCACAAGAUAAAACUAAAUUUUGUCCAUUUUUACCAGAUGAUUCAAAAUUUACCAUUUGAUUCAUUUCUUAAUAAAACUGCCUGUCAAUCUACUAGACUAAAUAAGAAUAUAAAUAAUUCAAUAUUAUUUAUAUAAACAAAAUCAAUGGAAAAUGACAAUUUUAUCUAAUUUAAUCAAUGCCUGUGACUUAGCAAAGAUAUUCAGUUCAAUUUAACAAUCUUUAUGAAUUAAUAUUUCCUUAGGAAUUAUGUAGCUAAAUUAUAUUAAUAAUCCAUAUUUAUUGAAGGGUAAAGGCCACAGAGUGAGACUAAAUUAUCUAGGUCCAGAGAAAAGGCAUCUAGGGCAAUAAGGAAACGAAACAAAUAUAACAAAUAACUUCUAAUUUACAGAUCACUUAAUGUAAGCUCAGCCAAGAACAAUGCUUACUACAUAAAUAUGUUCCAAGCAACUAUGAGACACUGUGUGAAGAUUUCAUGUGCAUUUCACUGUCUAUUUAAUAGAUUAAACAACCAUAUAAGGUAAGAGGUAUUAAAAAAGCUAAAGAGCAUAUGAAAAAUAGGGUUUUACUAACUUGUCCAAGGUCACAUAACUAAUAAAUGAAAGAGAGAGCAUUGGAUUUCAGGUUUGUGUAAUUCAAAAUCUAUGCCCCUUAUCACUAUUAUACAUUGCCUCCUAACUAUAAUAAUAAUUUAUUGAAAACCCAUUUGUCUAAGAUGGGAUUUUCUGGAUGAUAUGACUAUAUUAAAAUAACAUUAAAUAGUUGAAAAAUGAAUUUAAAUAAUUAGUUUCUUCAUGUAAAACAUUUUUUUCUCAUUUUUUAAACUUGAACAUCUAAAACACUUGCUUCUGUAAUUCCACUGAACCACAACCUAAUUUCUGUUAUUCCAAAAAGAAAAUAAAAACUCAUGGGCUCUGGGUACACUAAAAGACUCCAAAAAUUAUAACUUUGUAUUAAUCAUAUAAUAGUCUUUCAUAACACCAGCCCCAAACAUACCAAACUGGUAGUUAGACAGUAUGUAUGCAACAUUUUUUGUGUGAUUAACUAUGUUUCUAAAUUUCAGCUAUUAUUUCGGAUGUUGGAAAACAUCAGUAAACCCCAAAGUUGUGUUUAUUGGCCUAUAGCUUACAUGAACUGAGUGUUUAAUAUGUAUUUGGUACUCUCCUAAUCGGUACUUCCAUUACCUAUGAAAGUAAUGAUUAUAACAAGUCAUCAUGCAAAAGAAUCAUCUUUUCAAUAUAUUGAAAAUGUGUGUUUCAGACUACUGAAUUCUUCCCUGUAAAUCUAGGAUAGAUCUAGGAAUUGGCACUUUCAAUGUAUUUUAGUUAACACUGAUGCAGAUUGUCCAUUCACUCCUUUUAGAAACACUACAUUACAUCCUUACAAGUCUAUGAAGUAUUAAAACAGAAAUGACUAUUAUUAUUGCUACUUCAGUGAUGAAGAAUCUCAAAGUUUGAGUUAAGUGAUGUAUCAAAACUCUGACCUUGUUAGUGAAAUAUUAAGCCCAGUUCAUCUCAACAUUAUUAACCUCUGCUCACACUUGUCUAAAUUACUAGUUUUUAAGUCUGGCUGUUCAUUAACAUCUCUGGGGAAGAAUUUCACCCAUUCCUGAGCUCCAUGCUCAGAGUUAUCAUAAUUGUUCUGGAGUUUCCAGGCAUCAGCAUACUUUUAAAAUUCUUCCUAAGUGAUCCUAAUGUGCAGACAGAUUUGACAACCACGGAGCAACUAAGACUGUACCACAGUAAAAUUCCAAAACUUCCCAUUUAUCCAGUUUGAAAGAUUAUAGAUUAGAAAACAUGAUGACAAGCGUAGAUUAUUCUGUGUUGUUUCCUGCCCUUUUUAGGUAUUUCAAUACUAUUAUUGUUGUACUGAAAAAUAAAAGUUCCAGUCAAUUUUUAUGGUUUUGCUGGGUUUAUAGAGAACACUCUGCAUGCCUUCCUAUUGAAUCUGGGACUCUCGUUUUUGGAGAACUACGUAAGUGAUCUGUUUUCCUGAGUCUUGACAUAUGCACCUUAUUAAUUAGAGACUAUAAAUCCACUUUUUAACACAUAAAAUCUAAUGAUGACAUCUUUGUAGAUAUUGAAAUUCAAGAAUAUAAACAGCAUUGCCUUCAACCCACUGCUGUUUGUAAACUGAGCUGCCUUCCUCUUUCCACAAAAUUAACUAAACAUAUUCAAGAAAGAAGGAGAAAAACUAUCAGUUUUCCACAGUGGACUUUUUUUCAUAAAUCCUUCAAAUGUCAGCAUGUAUGCCUUGUCUCAUUUAGUCAUAGCCCAUAUGAUCCAAAUCUCCAAUUUAUUUGUUUUUCUUUUUCCAAGAACUGGGUACUUUAAAAAUUUGUCAAAUUUUUAAAUUUCAGAUAGCUGAAACAGAACAAGUCAUAUUGACUUGCUCUAAGUGUUUAAAAGGUUUGAGGUUAUUGAUAUAGGCCUCAAUAUAUUUCCACAAAUGAAAUAAUGUAUUUACAUAGAGAUCUAAAAAGUGUACGAAACUUGAGAUAGCUAUUUGAGUCAAGAAAAACAAGGACUGUGAAUAGUGUAAAUUAUGUAAAUAUACACAGAUAAUUCACACACACAUAUUCACACAUAGUUCCAAGGAUUCCCCUAUAUCAAUUCCAACUCAAAAUUUCUCAGUCAUUUCUGGCUAAAGAGAAACAUGUCCAUUUAAUUAAAAUCACUUUUAAAAAAUCUGAUCAUCUAUUCUUUAUGAGAUCAAUGAAUACAUUAUUUUAAUGCUCUGUCUUAUUUAAAAUAUUUUUCUACAUAGUGUUGCUAGCUAAAAUGAGGCUUUUUUAAAUAAAUGGAUACACCUCAAAAUAAUAAUUUGAGAUCAGUUUCAUCUUGGACUUAUAUGAUUUUCAGAUUUUAUCUGCAUAAAAUUAGAUUUUCUGGAAAACUAAUUUGUAUUACUUAUUUUCUCUGUAUAAACCUUGCUGAAAAUGAAAACUAAUAAGCUUGAAUUUAUGGGUUUUAUGUAUUUUAAAACGUAAUGUAUAGAGAUUUCUUAUAAUUAUUUGACAGCUUCAAGAUAACCAGUUUUUUCUUUAAACAUUCCACUGAUUAAUACAAAAAGUAACAUUUUUUUCAUGAGAUGAAAUGAAACUUGUUCUUAGGCAAACAUCACUUAAUUAAAGCAAUUUAUAGUGAAUACACUCAAUUAACUGAUUAUGAACCUGCAACACCAAAAGAUUUACCAGAUUUGUUCACAAUUUUACUGCUAGCUGAUAUCAAAUAAGAAAAAGACAAAUCAAUGUUAUAUCUUCAGGAACUAAUAACUUUUUUCAUCCUGCAAGUUUGUGAAUUCAAAAAAACUAUUUUCAAAUAACUAAGAAUUUUUUUAUUAUUAUACUUUAAGUUUUAGGGUACAUGUGCACAACUUGCAGGUUUGUUACAUAUGUAUACCUGUGCCAUGUUGGUGUGCUGCACCCAUUAACUCGUCAUUUAACAUUAGGUAUAUCUCCUAAUGCUAUCCCUCCCCCCUCCCCUGACCCCACAACAGGCCCAGUGUGUGAUGUUCCCCUUCCUGUGUCUAUGUGUUCUCAAUGUUCAGUUCCCACCUAUGAGAACAUGCAGUGUUUGGUUUUUUUGUCGUUGCAAUAGUUUGCUGAGAAUGAUGGUUUCCAGCUUCAUCCAUGUCCCUACAAAGGACAUGAACUCAUCAUUUUUUAUGGCUGCAUAGUAUUCCAUGGUGUAUAUGUGCCACAUUUUCUUAAUCCAGUCUAUCAUUGUUGGACAUUUGGAUUGGUUCCAAGUCUUUGCUAUUGUGAAUAGUGCCGCAAUAAACAUACGUGUGCAUGUGUCUUUAUAGAAGCAUGAUUUAUAAUCCUUUGGGUAUAUACCCAGUAAUGGGAUGGCUGGGUCAAAUGGUAUUUCUAAAAGAACUAAGAAUUUUUAAAAAGAUUUUGGUUAUGUAAUUAGAGUGCACAAUAGAAUAAAACAGCCAGGUUUUAUAUUUUCACUGGCAAAUGAUAAAGAGACAACUUUGAUUAAAUACUCAUAAUUUUUAUAAAACCUCCAAAGUUUCAAAGUAGGUAGAUGAUGGGUAAUAAUUAAAUAGAGUGACAGUGUUAUAUGCCAGGUUAAAAAAAAAAGAGACAUGCGGCUUCAUCCACAAGCUUAGCAAAAUAUGAGAAAGUAAGAAACUGUGGCCAAAUCAGAUAAACAUAAAUGAGAAUAAGUUGUAGAAACUGACCUUCAAGUUAAUAAUUAAAUCAGAUGGUAUCAUUUUCCUCCAUCUGGUUAUUAUUGUUUAGAUUUUUAAUAGUACAAAAAUAAAUGUUUUAUGAAUUAUUUUGGAUGCAAUUACAGUAAAUAACCAUAAUAUAAAAUGUCUCAUAAUAGGAAAAUAAUGCCUGACACUUUUAAUUACUUAACAUACCUUUUUAUACAUUUUUUAAUGUCAUUUAUUUGGCAGCUAUUUAAGGAGUGCCCUCUGUAUCCUGGGCCAUCUCUUUCUAUCCAGAGUCCUACAAGUCACCUUGUAUCAUUAUUAGGAUAUAGUAUAAAAAUUUGUCCACUUUUAAAUGGAGAAAUAAUACAGAUAAGUAAAAAAAUGAUGUAAUAAUUUGAGUUCUGUACAUGACUCAGAGACUUGGACAGAAUUGACAAUUCUAAGUUUUUAAGUUAAACCAAAGCUGAAAUUUCUAAUCAUUUAGAAGCUAGGAAAAGUUCUGUUUCAAAUUCAAUUGAUCACUUCAUGAACAGUUUGUUCAUAAUUACUUCUUCUCUGCCUUUCAGCGUAGUCUUGUUCAAUUGUUCAGAGUGUCCUUUUUUUUUUUUUUUUUUUUUUUUGAGACAGAGUCUCACUCUUUUGCCCAGGCCGGACUGCAGUGGCACUAUCUCCGCUCACUGCAAGUUCCACCUCCUGGGGUCACGCCAUUCUCCUGCCUCAGCCUCCCGAGUAGCUGGGAGUACAGGCGCCCGCCACCACGCCCGGCUAAUUUUUUGUAUUUUUAGUAGAGACGGGGUUUCACCUUGUUAGCCAGGAUGCUCUCGAUCUCCUGACCUCGUGAUCCUCCCGCCUCGGCCUCACAAAGUGCUGGGAUUACAUGCGUGAGCCACCGCGCCGGGCCCAGAGUGUCCUUAUUCCCAAGUUCGUGAUUUUCAUAAUAGUAAGAGAACAAAAAACAAAUCUUACAAGCAAUAAAUUUUAUAAAUAGUCUUCUCUUAAGAUGCAGAACACCAACAUGGCACAUGUAUACAUAUGUAACAAACCUGCACGUUAUGCACAUGUACCCUAAAACUUAAAGUAUAAUAAAAAUAAACAAAUAAAUAAAUAUUCAACACCUCACUCUAAUUGGAAAGGAAAUGUGCCUACAGAAGUUAAAGCACAUUCUAUGAGUUUUAAUCUUAGGUGCCAAGAAGGAUCCAUGACCUCCACAUUUGACAGAGAAUAGAAAGACUCCACGGUUUUCAUCAUAAUCCAAGGGAGGUCAGUAAUAGUUUAUUUGCAUUUCUCGAGGGCUCUCUGGGGCCUCACUAUCUUACAUAAAAGUGAGUUUAAUCAUAGGACUUUCAGACAUUAGCCCACAGAUGGGACAUAUAUUUUGGGAUGGAGAACUUUUAAUAAAUCACAUUACCUAGGUGGCCUCUCAUUCUACUUCUCCAUAUGGCAGACUCUGUAGGAAAAAAAAAUGCUUCCUAUAAUGUUUCUUCUUUACCACAGAACUGUCAGAGGAAACAGCCGAGAAAAACUUAAAACUAAGCUACAAUAUUUGGCAAAAAUAAUGGUAGUUUUCAGAGGAGAAGCAAUUUUUCUGGCGUAUAUGUAGGAUAAGAGUAUCUUACCUUCCUUAAAUAAUGUUAUCUUUACCAGUAAACAUGAUGUAUUUGCCUUAACCUAGUCAAUUUCCUUUACCUGAAUUCCCUUAAGUUUAAAAUCAUAAUUUUUCAAGAUAAGGUUCUAGUCUUAGGAAUGUUGCUUAAGAACCUGAAAUAGAAUGAUACUAUUAUUUCAUCCUGGUAUUAAAAUCUCUAAAAUUUUCUACAAAACUAACAUUCUAUGUGUUCUGUGGCCAAUGUGAUAAUAAAUCCUUGCAUAACAACAGAGAAAAAUAUCCUAUACAUUUGUCUUACAUUUUUGCAAAAUAAAGAAAAUAUUUUGGAAUUAAACUAAUUUCAAAAUCCAAGAAUUUCUAUGAAAGAAUUUUUUAGCAGUAACCACAGAUGAAAAGAAUAUCAUUUAGUAUCUCUUCAUAGUGUCUUUAUAACAUAAUCUAAUCAUUGGUGUUUUAUAAUCUUUCAUAAUUUUUCAUAUAUUUGAUAAAUCCUGAUGUUGGGUUUAUUUCUGUUGAAACACCAGUAAUUGUUUUAUGUCACUUUGACUUUUUUCUAUAGUUUUGUUUUCUGCUUGUUUAUCUAAAUUAUCAUCAUAGUUGUAAUCUGAGAACUAGGCAAACAUAGGUACUUUUGACUAUCACUUUGGGGUGAUACUAUUUACCCAAUAUGAUUUUUUCCCAUUUUACUCUUGAAGUAUCCUGUUGCUUACUCUUUUGUGUAUGCAUACAUUUGAAACAUAUGACCUCCCAAGCAUUCUACUUUCUCUUAUUUUACUUAUUGUGUUGGCUUUACUGUUUAUGUAUGAUUUAACAUAAAUAAUUAUUUUGUUUUCUCUCUCCCAUCACCCACCCCAUUUACACGUUACAACAAGACUUCAUCAGCCCUGGGGUCAUGAUUUGAAUUAUAUUAUCUGUGCCAUUAAACAACCUUGAGCCUCAAUAAUAUCUGUUCAGAUUUUUUCAAUGGCUAUUGUUCAUUGAUAAUUACAUUCUGGGGACAUGCCAGAAUGAAAUCUCAUGGUUUCUCAGCCACAAAGAUUUGUUAAGAAUCAAAUUCAAAGGUAUUUGACUUGGUAUUUAUGAUUCAUGGCAAACCCAAGCAUAAUCUUUAGCAGAUCUUUAAGCUUCCUGAGCUUAUAAGCAAACUCUGUGUGUGUCUGUGUGUAUGUGUGUGUGUUCCUAUGUGGGUAAAUUUUUCUUGAUAGCAUCUCUGUGCUUUCAUCAUUAUCAAAAAGUUUCAGGACCCCAAAAUGGUUAAGAAACACUGACUAUGUGCUAGUUACAUUUCAAGAAUAUAUUUCUACAUAAAAAUGUUGUAUUUAUUCUAAAGGCAAAAGCCAUGGAACAAUGUGUACUUUUAAAAUAUUUAUGAGGAAUUAAAAAUUCAAUUAUUAUAAUUUUUCCAUUUUAAAAUUUUAGGAUGUGAUUUUGUAAUAGCCUCCAAAAAACAUUUAAAGCACCCAAGUAAUUAAACUAGUAAAAGUUCCUUAUAAACCAGAAAGCAAAACUAUUUUCCAAAUGGGCAAUAAAAAUAUUACUUUUGCAUGUAAAUAGUUGUUUAAGUGAAUUUAUUGUUUAUAUUAAUUAAAUUCUUUUGGACAAUUUGCCACUUAAAAAGAUCAGUGUUUGAACUCUAGGAAAUACUUGUUUAUGUAAUUUUUUUUGCAAGUAGGUAAGAAAAGUAUAUUUCAUUAUCAAAUAGCUACCCUGCAAUACUAACAUAAACAGCUAUUUACCCAUUUAGACUUAACUAUUCAGUCAAUUACACAACAGUCUUACCAUGUUAUUUAAUGAGUGGAACAAAAAUAAAGGUCUUUAUAACAGAUAAAAUAUUUCAUUUAUAUAAUGAAAUAAAAUAUCUUGGGAUUAAUAAAAAUAAUGAUUUUUUUCAUCCUAUGUAAAAUGUAGUUGAUAGCACUGAUAUAUUAAUAAUGUUAUGGGUGAAGUUUACAGUUCAUUACAAGUUGAAUGUACUUAAACAAUCUACAUCCUUCACUCCUUCAUUCAAUCAUUUAAUUCAGCCAUUCCUUAUUUGACAAAUGUGAUUUGUCAAAUCACAUUACUAAAUGUAUUAUACAUUUAGUAAUAACCAUACAUAUCAUGUUGAAUUGUUGUGAGGAUAAAAAAGUAAACAAUGUUCAAUUAUUGUUAAUAUUUUAUUUUAUAAUUAAUUAUAAAAUUUUAUAUAAUUAUAUAAUUAUAUAAUUAAUUAUAUAAUUUUACUUCAUUGGAUGUUGUAAAUUGCUCUGGUUUAGCCUUUAGACAUUUGAAUCAAAAUGGUCAAAUUAGUCUCUAAAUUCAGACAUUGACUUUGUUCUGCAGAUCUCAAAACGAAAGAUAUGUUGGGAUAUUUAGACCAGAAUGCAUGUGAAAAUACUACAUGAAUGAAUGUAUUUGACACUGAUCUUGAGAUGACAAUCUACAGUCCUACAAUAAUUAUUCUAACUCCAUGUUCUCUUUCGUGCACACUAGCUAGAGCACAUCUCACCCACUGACAUUGGAAUCUAUCCUUUCGUAAGUUAUUUUUAACGUCUUAGGAUGACUUUUAUAAAUUGAAGAUUUAAGAGUUUCUAAGGGGACUGUAGGUAUAUUCUACUGUUGUGUUUACCACAUGUUCCAUUCAGAUACACAAAAGAAAUGAAUAAAACUGGACAUAGCACACAGUCUCACUGCUUUGAUGGGCAAUGAUUUUUGACAAUGGGUAAUUAACUCUUACAUCAUUAAGUUCCAUCGUCACAGAAUAACCUUAGAAUCCUAAUAAAAUCCCACGGCUUCAAAUUGUAUUUAAUAGCUGCCAAUCCAAGCCUCCUGACUAUGCUAAUCUAUUAUUUAGAAUAAAUGAAAAGUGUGUAUCAAUUUGCCUAUUAUAAUACAAAGUGGGAACUCUCAUGCCAACAAGGUUAGGCCAGAAAAAUUCAAAUAAAUUGGAGAUGUGUUUUGAUACAUUUUCUUCCGUUGCUCUUAUUGUAUCUGACAUGGAAAUUUCCUUAGGGUGAAGUUUAUAUAGUGACAAGCAUAUACAAUAUUCUUGAGGUAUUAGGCCACAGUCAGAAAAAGAGAAUAUAGGAGGAAUUAUGUGGUAGAGGAUGAUAAAAGAUUAGAAGUUGAAACUAUACCAUAUAUAAUUUUAUAUAUAUACAUAAUUAUCUUGAUUAUAACCUAAAUUGUAAAAUCUCAAUAUUAUUAGUACCAUCCCCAGACACAUUCCCUUUGUUUCUUAAAUUUUUACUCUCCAAAAAUGGGAAUCACAGAAACAGAAGAUGCUUAAAUGUUCAUGUUAGGCAUUUUUUUCUGAGCUCAUAAAAGAUUAUUUGAUCAUUUAAUGUGUUUUUCUCUCCAAUAAGACUGUAAAAAGUUCAGUGUUUCGAGGCUGCUAAACAAUGCCCAUAGAGUUGACAGUCUCAAGAAUGACUGGAAAAUGAUGGAGUUGGAUGCUAUAGGUCAUACUUUAUAAAUCUGACUGAAGGAGAAUUAGAAUACUAAUGAGAGUCAACAACAAUUUUCUUACCUGCUCCCAAUUUGUAAUUCUUGCCCUGGUGGCACAUAUAUUACAAGGAGAAUAUUGUUUUCAAAUUUAUAGUCAGAAAGUCAUUUAGGUGACUGACUUUGUUUUUUAAAUAGUAAGUUGACUGUCUUGUUUAAAAAUGCAUAGUGCCCUGGAAAGUUAUGUGAAUACAAUGAUUUAUUUUAAGUAAAGGGUAGUUUUAUAAAAUAAAGUGCCAAACAUCAUAUAAAUAAAUAUUUACAGGCUCAGUAUCAAUCAAAUCAGUGGUAAGAGUGAAUUUUUUCAAUGUAUGACUUUCAUAUCAAAUUUUUUUUUGGUGAUUCAGCUUAAUAGGAGUUUAUGGUAUGGGCCCAUUCACGUUAUAUCCAAAUAAACAAAAAUUAUCUAGAGUUGUUCAUGCCAUCAUUUCCUUCAGCACAGUCUUCAAAGUAGUUUUCUCAUUACCCACUUUGAAAGAUAUUUCCAAGGAGAGGAUAAUGCAACCCAUUCUAUAUGUGAAUAAUGGGUGGGACACAGGCCAAUAAUCAUGAUCCAAAUUAGUCUGAAAAUCAAAGGAGUAAGGGGAGAAAAAAAGAAUGAAGGAUUAAUUGAUUUGCUGAGAGCAUGUCACAUGCUAAUUGUUGUUUUACAUUUUUCAUCUAUGUCUCUCAUGUGAUUCAGACCACAAAUCUGUGUGAUAAGUAUUGUUAUCCUUAUUCUACCAAUGACGACACAGUAGUGAAGUCAUAAUUCAGACUUGAAAUUCUGUCUUCUCUCAAUUUUCAUCCCAAAAUUAGAUAUCCUCGAUGCCAGUUCGGAUUCUCUUAUUCAAUGAGAAAAUCACUUCCUUUUCGGCCCUUGUCAUCUUUGUCUGUAUAACAAGGGGAUAAGACAAAGACGUUUGAUGAAAAUUUCUUCAAGUUGUAUCAUGUUUUUAUUCUUAGUGGGUAGUCCUUUGUAAGUCUGCAUACGGCUGGCUGGUGACACAAUGUGGGCACCAUAGACCGAAAAAUAAAAUUACUGAAAAGGCGAAGUAUACUUUCCAAAAAUUAGACUCUAAUCAAUGUAGUCCGUGCAACAAUUUUCUUUAAUACCGAAUUGCAUUUUAUAUAGCUAUUUGCACAGAUCUUCACAAUAAAACCAUAAGAAAAGGAGAAUAGGAUAUUAUCUUCACAGUUCUACAGAGGAGUAAAAAAACUGACCUUGAUCUAAAUAAGUUUAGAGGUGGAUUUUAAUCCUUUAAUAAGCAAAAGACAUAUAAUAAAAUUGAUAAAUGACAAUAUCAAUACUUUAUCUAAAAGUAAUUUCAUAAAGAAACAAAGCCAAAAUUGAUUCAGUUAACAUAAAAAAGAGUUAACCCAGAAGAAAACAAUGAAUAUUGAUCUCGAUUUCAGCAAGCAGAAAAUAAAAAAAAAAAAAAAGCAGAAAAAAGUGAGAAAUUGUUAAGGUGAGUGAAAGAUGAGCGGCGGUUGCUCUGAGAAACUACAACACAACUUAUUUAUUCAAGUGGCUGGGUCAGAUUUAAAGAUGUGAUUUCAAUAACUUUUUUGAAUAGAGUGUUGUACCUUUGUCUAAAGUAGUAAAAUUCAUUUGAAUUAAAGCUGAAUAUGGGUUUUCCUCCUCAAAUCCAAUUCAAUUCCAAGGUUUGAAAUUGCAGGGGCUCCUGAGAAGAAAUGGCAAAAAUAAAAAAGAGAAAGAGAGAGAAAGGGGAAGAGAAAAGGAAAAAAGAAAAAUCUAUAACUUGAAGCCCUGUAAAGCAAAGAUUUACCAAACUUUAGAUUUUAUACCCCCUCUUUUUUCAGCAUAUCCAAAUAAAUUUACAUGAUCUUAUGAGUGUAAAUCUUCUAGUCUUCAUGAGAUUUUUCCAGCUUUUCUGCCUUUUAGAUUGACAUUUCUAGUUGCUUAAGGUUUCUUCUUCAAAGCAAUGGGUAUAAAACAUGUGAUUAUUAUUAAACAGUUAUGGAAAAUACCAUCUUUAUUCCACCACUUUAUCAGGUAGAACUUGAAGGUAAAAUAAAGUUUGGAUGCUGAGUCUACAUGUAUUGUAUUGUAUUGUAUUGUAUUGUAUUGUAUUGUAUUGUAUUGUAUUGUAUUGUAUUGUAUAGUGGUUACCAGAGAUUUAAUAACAUAGCAGAAGUAACUGAAUCGCCUCCUCUGCCCUAUGCACUUGUAUUUUUUUUAUUUCAAAAAUGCCAGGAAGAUAAGUGUAUGCAAAAAUAUAAAGUUUGUAAAAUUUUAUACAACUUAAUCUAUUUGAUCAUUAGUUAAGUAAGCUUAACUAAAUUAAAAAUGUAUUUUAUUGCUACUUUUUUUAACUCUCUAAAGAAUACAUUUAUGUUUUUGAAGGAGCUUUAAUUUAGUAACAGUUAAUCUUUUUAUUAAUUUUAGUAAAAAUAAUCAUACCCUUUUAAUAAUAAAAAUUAAACUUUAAGUCUUUAAAAUUGCUAGUUGUAAGUGAAUUUGUCAAAGAUUAAUUCAUAGUUGCCAACACUUACUGAACAGGUAGAUAAAAUUAACUUUGUUUAUUUAACAAAUAACUUGGUGCUUUCUAGUUAGUUUAAAAAUAUCAAUAAUUGUUUCCUCACAUGUAUUUAUGUCCUUCCUUCACAGCAUAUAGUCAACCAUAGAGACUCAAUGUAAAGUAUUAUGAUAAUUUAUAUGUCUGAGAAAAUAAGAAGAUUGAUUCAUUGAAAAGUUAAAUGAAUUUGAGAUACAGGUAUUUCUGACUGCCUAGUUACACUGUAUGAAAUACUUUAAAAACUGGCCAGGCGUGGUGGCUCAUGCCUGUAAUCCCGGUACUUUGAGAGGCCAAGAACUCCUGAAAUCAGGAGCUCAAGACCAGCCUGACCAACAAGGUGAAACUCCAUCUCUACUAAAAAUACAAAACAUUAUCUGAGUGUGGUAGAGCACGCCUGUGGUCCUAGCUACUCAGGCGGCCGAGGCAGGAUAAUCACUUGAAUCUGGGAGUCGGAGGUUUUGGUAAGCAGAGAUUAUGCCACUGCACUCCAGCCUGGACAACAGAGCAAGACUCUGUCUCAAAACAAAAACAAGCAAACAAACACACACACACACACACACACACACACACAAAAACACUUAGAAAAACUGUAAACAAUUCAGUCUUGUAUUUGGAAGAAUGGUGACUUGUAAAUUUUGCUGUACAUUAAUGACAAGUCUCUCACUCAAAUAAAGAUAACCUAAGUAAAAUAAUUUAUGUCAGAUGAAAACAUUCCAAAUUUUCUUGGAGAAAAAGCAACAAAAGCCAAUAAAUAAAGGUGGUUCCCAUUACCUAUUUAAUUAUUUAAUAUCUUAAACUAUUAUUAAAUGCAUGCACCACCUGCACUACCCUGACCGAUUAACCCCUUAGCUGAAGGAGUUCAGUUUGUAUUUUUACCAUAUGAUCUGUCUAGAUUCACUCUUUUCAGGAUUGAUAGAUUUUUUUUUUCUUUUUUCUUUUUUUUUUUUUUUUGCUUUCUUAUUCAACUCUACAGUAAAAGAAAAUCUGUGGUUUUAUUUGACAUAACAGAGCUAUCUUCAGCCAUAGCUAGAAGGAGGAUAGUAGGAUAAAGGUCAAUUUUUGUCUUCCUUCACAGCUAACAGAUAUAUGUAGCAUGCUUAAUAAUAACUCUCAAAGUCUGUUGCUCAACCUCCCAAACCAUUAAUUUCCUUCUAGCCACUGCUAGAGUUCAUGCAUGUCAUGAAAGGAAGGCUAGAGGGACAAUUUCUGUAUGCAUAUCUCUGGCCCAUGCCCUUCAAUGAGACCCAAAUAUAAUUAAUUUCUGGGAUUUUUGCAAUAAAUAAUAUGAGAUGACCUCAUUAUAGAAUGAGGGGCAAGAUCCUUGGCCUUGGUCUUUCACAAAUAAUAUGACUUUAUUUACAGAUGAAGAAAAUAAAAUAAAAAUUAAACAUAAACUUUCCUCAACUUCCUGCUUUUAGCCCAGGUAGCAUGUUAUUACUAUUUCUUUUAUAAACAACUGAGUUCUGACUAACAGUCUUUAAGAGGAGCUGCUAUGAGGAAAUAUAGAUAAUAACAAAAUAAUAACAUAUUUUUAAAGCUUUGCCAGCAGCAAAGGGCUCGCAUCUACAUACUCUCAUUUUAUGUGUCCAACCAAUGGUUCCACAUAGCCAUGAAAUCAGCUGUUACAAUAGGAAGACCACCACUGAACAGUUUUGUAACUCAUUUCAGAAUUGACUUUGGUAUGUGCUUAUUGGUGUAUUUCUGUGCUUGUGUCAAUUCAACAAAGCUUCCCAAGCAAGGUUACUUCAAACAUUACUUGGGCCACGGUAAAAGAAAAAUAAAAUUCUGUUGAUUCAGAGUCACCUUCAAUCUCAUGUCAUAAAUUAUGUUUCUCUAGUCUUUGAUAUUGUUUCACAUGUGCAUGAUUAGAUUGGUUGAGGAUAGACUUUGGGCUCAUGAUUUAUUGACUAAUUAUGUGGUUUUCCCACUGUAGCUUGGGUUAAAUCUUACAAGACAGGCUGAAAACUGAAAUUGUUAUGACAUUUUUGUUUUCUCUACACCAUACCAAGUAAUGCUGUUUGAUUGAAUCAAAUAUUUUCUAAAGACUAAAUGUAAUCCAAAAAAUGAUCUGUAAAUGUUCCCAACAGGUGUCCCAAAACCAUAUUUUAGUAAGUUUUUCAAUUGGUCCAACAGUUCUAUAAAUUUUACCUUGAGGUAACUAAAAUGGAAACAUAAUGAAUAUAUUAUCUCUAUUGUCUAAGGACAAACAAAACACCGAAGUUAUUGAGAAUCAGAUUCCCAUGUUAGCAUAAAUGAGUCACCUAGUUUUUUCAACAAAACCAAGUAAUAAAUAAAUCAACACUUUCAGUUUUCUGCCAGUGUCACAGAUGGCAGCCAAUUGGUUUGAUUAAAAAUCUGAUGCUUGCAUGUUUGCAUAGUAAAAGACAGGGUUUUCAGGAAAAAAUCAUUAUACUUCUCACUGUGUUCCACACAAUGUUGAAGGUUAUGUCCAAAUUUGAAAAACAAAUCCAAUUAAACUAGCUACCAUACAAAUAUAUCUUUUGUUAUUGAAAGAGUGAUUUCAGUCGUGAUUUUUCAUUAAUCUAGUUUUGUAAAAAUCAGACUUCCUGUAAACCAAUUGAAAACCUCUACAUUUUACUAUAUGUAUUCAUGGACUUAAUUUCAUCAAAAAUACCAAUAUUCUCUGUGCCCUAACAAGUGUAAUUGCACUAACCUUGUAGUUGAUAUUUACUGAUUGAAAUGUAUAUACACAAAAAUUAUGUAAAACUGAUUAUCUAGAGGUUUCUUCAUUAGCUAGCACAAAUAGUUAUUGUAAACCUUUGUCCUGUAUUUUUUUAAAGUCUGCAACAUGGUGAACCAGUAUGCUUGAUGGCUUUAAUACCUGUGUCUGCAAUUUAUUAUUCAUUUGAAGCAACAAAUUCAGAAUUGUUUGAAAUUAUGAAGGCUAAACAGCAUAAAUACAUUGUGGUUUCUUUUAUAAA